GGCCAGGUCCCAGGAACCCAUAUUUAGAACUGAGGGUCCUAUGGCCCAGAACCAGGCAUCUGUACUUAAGAACCAAGCACCUGUGACCAGGACCCAGGCACCCAUCACUGGAACCCUCUGUCAGGAUGCCAGAUCCAACUCUCAUCCAGUGAAGCCCUCAAGACUCAAUGUCUUCUGUUGCCCCCAUUGUUCUUUGACUUUUAGCAAGAAAUCCUAUCUCUCCAGACACCAGAAGGCCCACCUCACAGAGCCGCCCAACUACUGCUUCCAUUGCAGCAAGUCUUUCAGCUCAUUUUCCAGGCUGGUCAGACACCAGCAGACCCACUGGAAGCAGAAGAGCUACCUUUGCCCUAUCUGUGACCUCUCCUUUGGGGAGAAAGAGGGCCUUAUGGAUCACUGGAGGGGCUAUAAAGGCAAGGACCUGUGCCAGAGCAGCCACCAUAAAUGCCGGGUGAUCCUGGGCCAGUGGCUUGGCUUCUCUCAUGAUGUCCCCACUAUGGCUGGGGAGGAAUGGAAGCAUGGAGGUGAUCAAUCUCCCCCCAGGAUCCAUACCCCCAGGAGAAGAGGCCUAAGAGAGAAGGCCUGCAAAGGAGACAAAACAAAGGAGGCAGUGAGCAUCUUGAAACAUAAAUAAAUGGCCUUUCUGACUGAGCUCUUUCUUUGUGUUUAGUUUUCCUGAGGACUGACCUCUGGGGUAAUGAGGCUGGAGUAGAGGGAGACAGGUGCGUGGAUAAGGAAGGAA